GUCACUGUUAUGGUCCUGUCAGGGUGCCGGCGUCGUGGUGCUUGGGUGGUCGCCACCAAGAAGACUUUGGUGGGGUAGUCUCGGGGCAGCUCAGCGGCCCGCUGUGCCCGUUUCUGGCCUCGCUCGCAGCUUGCACGUCGAGACUCGUAGGCCGCACCGUAGGGCGAGCGUGCGGGUCGCCGCCGCGGCCGCCUCGGGGUCUGGGCCCAGCCGCAGCCUCUUCUACCGCGGCCGGUUGGGAGUCGCCGCGAGAUGCAGCCUCCGGGCCCGCCCCCGGCCUAUGCCCCCACUAACGGGGACUUCACCUUUGUCUCCUCAGCAGACGCGGAAGAUCUCAGUGGUUCAAUAGCAUCCCCAGAUGUCAAAUUAAAUCUUGGUGGAGAUUUUAUCAAAGAAUCUACAGCUACUACAUUUCUGAGACAAAGAGGUUAUGGCUGGCUUCUGGAAGUUGAAGAUGAUGAUCCUGAAGAUAACAAGCCACUCUUGGAAGAAUUGGACAUUGAUCUAAAGGAUAUUUACUACAAAAUCCGAUGUGUUUUGAUGCCAAUGCCAUCACUUGGUUUUAAUAGACAAGUGGUGAGAGACAAUCCUGACUUUUGGGGUCCUCUGGCUGUUGUUCUUUUCUUUUCCAUGAUAUCAUUAUAUGGACAGUUUAGGGUGGUCUCAUGGAUUAUAACCAUUUGGAUAUUUGGUUCACUAACAAUUUUCUUACUGGCCAGAGUUCUUGGUGGAGAAGUUGCAUAUGGCCAAGUCCUUGGAGUUAUAGGAUAUUCAUUACUUCCUCUCAUUGUAAUAGCCCCUGUACUUUUGGUGGUUGGAUCAUUUGAAGUGGUGUCUACACUUAUAAAACUGUUUGGUGUGUUUUGGGCUGCCUACAGUGCUGCUUCAUUGUUAGUGGGUGAAGAAUUCAAGACCAAAAAGCCUCUUCUGAUUUAUCCAAUCUUUUUAUUAUACAUUUAUUUUUUGUCGUUAUAUACUGGUGUGUGAUCCAAGUUAUACAUGAAUAGAAAAAGAUGGUGUUAAAUUUGUGUGUAGGCUGGGAAUUCUUGCUGAAGGAAUUGGAGAAAACCUGUUGCUGCAAAAUUUUACAUGUUCCAGAUGGAAAGGGAAGUCUAAGCGCUUUUUAAAACAAUUUUUUUUUGUAUUUAAUUAAGCAAUUGCAGUUAUCUGGGAUUUUUGGGUCAGAAUUUUAAAUUCUGUUUGAUUCUCCAUAUUCCAGUGAAUAAAAUACAAAAGCAUUGUGUUUUUAAGAUUGUGUCGAUAUUCACCUAAAAACUUGUGCCAAAAGCACCUGGAUUGGUAAUUAUAUUUCACUUAAAGGGUAAAUUUGACAAUAUCUUGAUAAUCAAAAGUGCAAUUUUUUUCUUCAAAAUGUUUUCUCCAGCAUCACAGAUCCUGCAGAUAUAUAUUUAUAUUUAUACAUAUAUAUUUAUGAAAUAAUUCUUACUCACAAAAUAUAUUUCUGAUAAACAUUAAGAUAUUAAAUCUGAUGCACAAACUUUUUAAUUUGGCCAUUAAUCUUUUUUAUUUAAAAAUUUAAAUUUGUUUUUAAAAUUGUAUAUAGUUUUUAAAAUCUCACACAUGCUUCGAUACUUCCUUGUUAAGAAUUCUUAAUAACUACUAAAACUGAUUUUUAAUAGUUGCUGAUAUAUAUUUGGUUUGUUUGGGUAUACUUUUCAAAACCAUUUUUGAAUGUCCAAACAUCUGAUUUAAAGUUUCUGUUUAUCUUUCUGACCAAAGGAGCAAGAGGUAUAAUGGAUAUGGCAUUCAUUAAAAUCUUUACUAUGUACAAAAACAGUAAUAUUUACAGCAUCAGUAAAUAUUUUUAAGUGGUACUUCUAAAUCAUAAAAGUUGGGGAAAGAGACCUUUAAAAUCUUGUGGUGUUGAACAAUGUUAUAUGAAGUAGAAAAAAUAAAAUACUUCCCAGUUGUGUGUUUUGUUUUACAGCACCAUGUCCUGUAUUACUUGAUAUUUUAACAAGUAUCAGGUACUCUCUAACAAAUGUACAGUUUUUGCUAAGGGAAAUAUUAAGAAAUUUUUAUCAGUGAAAUAUUUGUUGCAAAUAAUUUCAUAGGUUUUUAGAUACACCUGUAGUUAAUAUUACUUUGUAAAGUAGGUAAAUCAUUUUAUUUAUGUCCAUAAAAUAUCAAAUGUCUGUUAACUAUUAGCAAAUUAUUGUAUUAUCCUUUCUGGUCUCACCUGGAAGAGUUUCCUGCUGUCCUCAGUAUGAUAACAUGGCGACCUCUUGGUAUGUAUUUCUUUAGCAAACUUACCCAUCAGGAAAUAUCCAGCACCUCUGAAGCAAACCUACAAAUGAGUGUGUUAUCAAGCCCAGCCGUCUUCCUUUCCCCUAAUCCCAAAAGGAAAGAAAGAAAAACUUAUUUUAAGCUGCAGAAAAAGUGUGGAGCACUUUUGAGCUAGAAUAAUGUAGAAAAUUACAUGUACUGAUUUUUUUAAAAACAGGUGAGAAGCACCAGAGGGACAGGACUUCUAGAAGUUAGAAUAAUAUGAAGUAAUCAGGAAAUAUCUAUGCCUACAGAAGCAGCAACCGUAAGAUAAACAUUUGUUACACUUAAGAAAUUGCUGAGGUUAAUACUUUGUUAUAAUGGAUUAUAAUAUUUGACAUUCAUAGUGUUGACCCUGGAAUCUUUCACAGAAAGCUUGGGGGUCAGGACCAGGAGGUAGAAUUUUACAAGGCAAUAAAUGAAGGUAUUUUAAGAUCACCUCUAUUAAAAAAUGGUUUAAUUUUUAAAAACUAUCAUUGCUUUAAGGUAUGAAUUUUAAAAAUCACUUAUAUGGAUCAUGUUUACUCCUAAUGAUAUAAGAUAAAAUGAGGUAUUUUUGUUCCAAAAAGUAUUUUAAAAUAGCAUUUAAUCUUGGGAACUAUCUUACUUAGGGUUUCUAUAAAUACAAAUUACAAUGUUUCGAACUCAACCAGUAUCAUUUUCGUGUGCUAAUGAGCAAAGUAGUUAGAACAGAUUGUCAGUUUAAAAACAGGAUUUGUAGGCCAGGCACAGUGGCUCACGCCUGUAAUCCCAGCACUUUGGGAGGCCAAAGUGGAUGAGCAGCUUGAGUCAGGAGUUUGAGACCAGCCUGGCCAACAUGGCGAAACCCCGUCUCUACUAAAAAUACAAAAAUUAGCCGGGCGUGGUGGCAGGCGCCUGUAUAAUCCCAGCUACUCAGGAGGCUGAGGCAGGGAGAAUCGCUUGAACCCUUGGAGGUGGAGGUUGCAGUGAGCCAAGAUUGUGCCAUUGCACUCCAGCCUGGGUAACAGAGCAAGACUCUCUCAAAAAAAAAAAAAAAAAAAAAAAAAACCAUGAUUUGUAGAUGUGUGCAAGACACAGUACUGCUAUGGCUAAUAAUGGUAAGAUGACCCUAAUAAUGUCCUCUCCUUGAAUUUUUAUAUAAUAAUAUUUUCUGAGUCAUAACUAAUUUUUUAAAUAAUGAUUUCCAAUCUAAUUAUUAAUUAGAAUUUUGUUGUUGUUGUUUGAGACAGAGUCACUCUGUCACCCAAGCUGGAGUGCAAUGGCACGAUCUCGGCUCACUGCAAGCUCUGCCUCCCGGGUUUGCACCAUUCUUCUGCCUCAGCCUCACGAGUAGCUGGGACUACAGGCGCCCACCACCAUGCCUGGCUAAUUUUUUGUAUUUUUAGUAGAGAUGGGGUUUCACCGUGUUAACCAGGAUGGUCUCGAUCUCCUGACCUCGUGAUCCGCCCGCCUCAGCCUCCCAAAGUGCCGGGAUUACAGGUGUCAGCCACCGCACCAGGCCAGUUCAUUAGAAUUUUUAAAACAGGCUGGGCAUGGUGGCUUACGCCUGUAAUCCCAGCAGUUUGGGAGGCCGAGGCAGGUGGAUCACCUGAGGUUGGGAGUUUGAGACCAGCCUGACCAAUGUGGAGAAACCCCAUCUCUACUAAGAAUACAAAAUUAGCCAGGCAUGGUGGUGCAUACCUGUAAUCUCAGCUACUGGGGAAGCUGAGACAGGAGAAUUGCUUGAACCCAGGAGGCAGAGGUUGCGGUGAGCUGAGAUCGCGCCAUUGCACUCCAGCCUGGGCAACAGGAGUGAAACUCCAUCUCAAGAAAAACACAAAAUACAAAACAAAACAAAACAAAAAAACAGAACUGGGCCGGGCGCGGUGGCUCACGCCUGUAAUCCCAGCACUUUGGGAGGCCGAGGCGGGUGGAUCACGAGAUCAGGAGAUCAAGACCAUGGUGAAACCCCGUCUCUACUAAAAAUACAAUAAAUUAGCCGGGCAUGGUGGCGGGCGCCUGUAGUCCCAGCUACUUGGGAGGCUGAGGCAGGAGAAUCGCUUGAACCCGGGAGGCAGAGGUUGCAGUGAGCCAAGAUCGUGCCACUGCACUCCAGCCUAGGUGACAGAGUGAGACUCCGUCUCAAAAAAAAAAAAAAAAAAAAUCAAAAUCUAUAUAAUUAAGCAUUGUUUUUUAAAAAGUAGUUUAGGAAGAUUUGUAAAGCUUAUGAACCAUUGUAAAACCUUAUUUCUAAGGUCUGUAAGACAGUUUUAUAUGUAAUAAUGUGUCCAUUUCCAGGAAUUCCCCAAAUACUCAUACAGCCAUUGAGCACCCCAAUCCAAAAUUCAGAAUGCUUCAGAUAAGAACAUUUUUGAGUGCCGAUGUGACACUUUAAAGGAAAUGUUCAUUGGAGCAUUUUGCAUUUCAGAUUUUUGGAUUAGGAAAACUCAACCACUGUAUUUCUGCACAUAUUCCAAAAUCUGAAAAAGUCUGAAACCUGAGAAACUCUGGUCCCAAGCAUUUUGGAAAGGGUAUACUCAAUCUGUAUUAACAUAGACUUCUAAAUUAGUGAAAAUUUGCAUUGAAUUAAAAUGUGAAGUAAAUAUUUUUGUUUAAAUAUUGUUUAAAAUUUAGUCAUUUAAAAAUUUUGUGAUGUAACAAAAUGUUGAAUGAAAUAAUGCUUCUACAACUUAAAAUUAUUUUUCAUAGUGAACAAAACUAGUUGAAUACUUCUAAAUAUUCAUUUUUGUUAGUGCACAUUUUAUCCAGUUUUAGGCUUUAGGGAAUUGUGACCCUUUUUUUUUUUUUUUUUUUUUUUUUGGAGACGGAGUCUUGCUCUCUCGCCCAGGCUGGAGUGUGUGGCGCAAUCUCAGCUCACUGCAACCUCUGAUUCCUGGGUUCAAGCAAUUCUCAUGUCUCAGCCUCCCUAAUAGCUAGGAUUACCGGUGCCCGCCACCACGCCCAGCUAAUUUUUUAAAUUUUUAAUGGAGACAGGGUUUCACCAUGUUGGCCAGGCUGGUCUUAAACUCCUGACCUCAGGUGAUCCACCCACCUUGGCCUCCCAAAGUGCUGGGAUUACAGGCUUAAGCCACCGUGCCCGGCACUUUUGUUUUUAAAAUAAUAUCUUACUUUCAUAUGAUUCUUUCAGACUGUGGUAUGGCAUUCUGAAGCAAGUCUUAACAGAGCUAAAAAUCACCCUUACCCAAUUCUCUGCACUGACAUAUGUACACAAAGUAAUAUUUUAUUAUUCUCCUUCAUAAAUGGUUUCUUUAAUUGAACCUUUGAGCCUUAUACUAUUUUUAAAUUUCCCUUUAAAAAUUGAAUUACAGCCAGGCAUGGUGGCUCAUGCCUGUAAUCCCAGAACUUUGGGAGGCCAUGGCAGGAGGAUUGCUUGAACCCAGGAGUUGUAGACCAGCCUGGGCAAGAUAGCGAGAUCCUGCCUCUGAAAAAAUCAUAAUAAUACUUUAAUUUAGAAAAUACCCUGAAUUAGAAGUGCUUCAUUCCUCAUUUGUGUACAGCUGUUCCUCUAUAUACGAAGGGGAUUGGUACCAGAACCACUGCAUACCAAAUUCCACCCAUACUCAAGUCUCACAGUCUUCCCUGCAGAAUCCAAGUAUACAAAAAGUAGGCCUAUCAUUUAUAUGGGUUUUGCAUCCUGACAGUACUGUAUUUUCAAUCCUAGUUUGUUUGGGAAAAAAAAAUUGUUUGUAUGCCUGGGUACAGUAUCAUACCUGUAAUCCCAGCACUUUGGAAGGCUGAGGCGGGAGGACUGUUUUGUGGCCAGGAGUUCAAAAUCAGCCUGGUCGACGUAGUGAGACCCCAUCUCUACAAAAGAAAAAUUAGCUGGGCAUGUGGCACCUGCCUGUGGUCCCAGCUACUCAGGAGGCUGUGAGGCAGGAGAAUUGCUUGAGCCUGGGAGGUUGAGGCUGCAGUGAGCCGCGAUCACACCACUGCAUGCCAGCCUGGGCGACAGAGUGAGACCCUGUCUCAGAAAAGAAAAAAAAAGUAAAAAUUGCAUGUAAGUUGACCCGCACUAUUCAAAUUUGUGGUGUUCAAGGUUCAACUGUAAUUUCCUAGCAGCAUUUUGUGUGUUUGAGAAUCUCUUGACACUCUUCAAGUAAAUCCCUAAAUUACAACUUUGACAUCAAAAAAGCUAGACAUUCCUACAUUUUUGCACUACAAUACAUAAAAACUCCCAUGCUGAUCGGUUGUGGGAUCGUGCCUGUGAAUAACCACUGCACUCCAGCCUGGGCAACAUAGUAAGUAAGACCUUGUCUCUUAAAAAAAAUACAUUCUGAAGAAAGUUCUACUUAUGAAUACAUUUUAUUUAUAACAAACUGGUGAAAAUUUUAGACCAAACCAUGUCUUUCUGGGUUGUAGUGAUUAAAAAAUGGUUAAGAGAAUGUUCCCUAUACAAGGCAUAUGUUAUUAAACAUGAAAUUUAGGAUUAGUUUUCUCUUUGAAAAUUCUUUUGAUAUGCUGAGGUUACAGUUUGGAGGUUACAUUAGAGAAAGAAUAUAGGGAAGAUGGCAGUGGUAAAACAUUUCCCUGCUUUACAUUUUUAUAUUGGCAGUAUCUUGGUUUCAACUUUUCUAUUUUCAGCAAGAUAUUUGCAAGUUUUUACUUUGAAGAUGUUUGGUUUAUAGUAGUCCAUGCUAUACUAAUGCUGUUGCUGAGAUAAUUAAGUUAGAUACUAAUAUGAAAAAGAAUAUUUGUGUAAAAUAUUUUGAAGUUGUAAUUAGUGUAUAUACAAGUUGUUAAUACUUACGAAAAAAGGAAGCAUUCCCACCUGUAAUAAUUUUGUUAACACUAGACUAUCAGUAAAUUAUCAAGAAUAAAAACCUUGGUUUUUCUGUAAUAUUUGCCACUGAGCAAUUUUUAUUAAAAACCAAACAGAAGUAUUUACACAAGAACAAGUGAAAUUACACAAAAUGAUAAUGGGGAGAAAUUUCUCAUCUGGUGAUAAAGGGAAAAAGAUAAUGUAAAAGCAGAUUGCUGCUAUUUGCAUAAUAAGCACUUGUUGAAGAAUAAAUGAUUAAGUUCAAUAUUUUUGCUCUAUUUUAUACCUACUCACUUUGGUGGAAUUAGUUCUCCAUGUAAAGUAUCUUUUUAAUAGUAAGCACCAUUUAAUAAUGAAACAACUCAUAUGUUUUGUAAUCCUUAUGGAGAAUUACUUCAUGUGAUAAUUAUAGUCUCUUCAUGGAAAACAGUAAAAAUACUCACGUUUAUGAUGAUGGGCCUAGGUACUAAAUUCCUCAUUCAAUCUUUUUUUACCAAAUGGUACUUAAUAAAAUCUUUUACCUUAUAAAAAUCUAUUUUCGGCCAGGCGCGGUGGCUCACGCCUGUAAUCCCAGCACUUUGGGAGGCCGAGGUGGGCGGACCACGAGGUCAGGAGAUCGAGACCAUCCUGGCUAACACGGUGAAACCCUGACUCUACUAAAAAUACCAAAAAUUAGCCGGGCGUGGCAGCGGGCGCCUGUAGUCUCAGCUACUCGGGAGGCUGAGGCAGGAGAAUGGCGUGUACCCGGGAGGCGGAGGUUGCAGUGAGCCGAGAUCGCGCCACUGCACUCCAGCCUGGGCGACAGAGCGAGAAUCCGUCUCAAAAAAAAAAAAAAAAAAAAAAAAAAAAAAAAUUAUUUUCAAAGGAUUGUGCUAGUGGUGGCCUGAAUAAUAAAACAUUGAGAAGAAACAGCCUUUGAAUUUGGCACCCUGAAUGUGAAGGGACAAUAGAUAUUAAUCACAUAUUUAUUAACCCCUUCCUGUAUGAACCUAGUACUGUGCUGAGUGUAGGGAUACAGUGAUAAUGCAAAAAAGACCCCCAAUAGGCCGGGCGCGGUGGCUCACGCCUGCAAUCCCAGCACUUUGGGAGACCGAGGCGGGUGGAUCACGAGGUCAGGGGAUCGAGACCAUCCUGGCUAACACGGUGAAACCCCGUCUCUACUAAAAAUACAAAAUUUAGCCGGGCGUGGUAGCAGGCGCCUGUAGUCCCAGCUGCUUGGGAGGCUGCGGCAGGAGAAUGGUGUGAACCCGGGAGGCGGAGCUUGCAGUAAGCAGAGAUCGCGCCACUGCACUCCCGCCUGGGUGACAGAGCGAGACUCUGUCUCAAAAAAAAAGACCGCCCCCCCCAAUAUACACACACCCUGACUUUAAUGAGCUUAUUUUGCUGGGGACUCAGCCAAUUAAUUUCACAAAUUGUAAAACUAUUUCAAGAAAUGAGAAAAAGAGGCCUGUGGUGGUAAGCAAGUAUAUAAAAGAAGCCUUCCUUGAAGCAACGAUGCUUAAGCUGAAAUCUUAGGGAAAAAUAAAAGUUAACUAGGCAAAGAAGGUAGGGAAGACUCUUUCAGAUAGAAUCGCAGUUUGUGAGUUUGCUUGGGGAAAAAAAUUUAAAAAUAUAAAAAGAAAACCAGUUUGAAGUUUAGUGGUUAAUGAAAUUGAACAGGUAUGUCAGCACCAUACCUGACAUUCUAGGCCAUUCUUUCUUUGUCAGAGCUUUUUUGUUGAGAUGGAGUCUCGCUGUCUCGCUGAGGCUGGAGUGCAGUGGUGCAAUCUCGGCUCACUGCAACCUCUGCCUCCCAGGUUCAAGUGAUUCUCCUGCCUCAGCCUCCCAAGUAGCUGGGAUUACAGGUGCCCAUCACCACACCCGGCUAAUUUUUUUGUUUUUAGUAAAGACGGUUUCUCCAUGUAGGCCAAGCGGGUCUUGAACUCCCAACCUCCGGUGAUCUGCCCACCUCAACCUCCCAAAGUGCUGGGAUUACAGGCGUGAGACACUGUGCCCAGCCUGUCAGAGCUUUUGAGUAGAAAUACGGUAUCAGAAAUGUGCUUUAUUUUAUUUUAUUAGACAAAGUCUUGCUCUGUUGCCAGGCUGGAGUGCAGUGGCGCGAUCUUGGCUCACUGCAACCUCUGCCUUCUGGGUUCAAGCGAUUCUCCUGCCUCAGCCUCCCGAGUAGCUGGGAUUACAGGCACCCACUGCCACACUCGGCUAAUUUUUGUAUUUUUAGUAGAGACGGGAUUUCACCAUGUUGGUCUCGAACUGCUAACCUCAGGUGAUCUGCCCGCCUUGGCCUCCCAAAGUGCUGGGAUUAUAGGCAUGAACCACUGCGCCCAGCCAGAAACGUGCUUUUAAUACUAAAGGCCAAGAUAUGCAAUUAUACUCUUGACAUAUAUUCAACCGAAAUGCAUGUACAUGUACCAUAAGAGACAUAUGUACAAGAAUGUGCACAGUUAACAUUAUUCAAAUAGCCAAAAACGGGAACAUGUCCAUCAACACAGAAUAGACAAGUUGGUAUAAUUACACAAUGGAAUCUUAUGCAGCAAUGAAAAUAAAUGAACUAAAGCCGCAUACAAAAACAUGAAGAAUUUCACAAGUAUUAUGUUGAGUGAAAAAGACAAAGAAUUUGUACUGUAUUACUUCAUUUAUAUGAAGUUCAAACACAGGCAAAAUUAAGCUAUAGUGUUUAGGGAUGCAUACUGAAAUGCAGUCUUUUAAAACAGCUUUAGAAUUCCUUGGCCAGGUGCGGUGGCUUACGCCUGUAAUCCCAGCUCUUUGGGAGGCAGAGGCUGGCAGAUCACCUGAGGUUGGGAGUUUGAGACCAGCCUGACCAACAUGGAGAAACCCCAUCUCUACUAAAAAUACAAAAUUAGCUGGGCGUGGUGUCGCGUGCCUGUAAUCCCAGCUACUCUGGAGGCUGAGACAGGAGAAUCGCUUGAACCUGGGAGGUGGAGAGUGUGGUGAGCUGAGAUGUCACCAUUGCACUCCAGCCUGGGCAAGAAGAGCAAAACUUCGUCUCAAAAAAAAAUAAAAAAAUAAGGCUCCAAGCGCUGUUGUGAGGGUUAAAUGAACUAGAUAAUUAAUGUAAUAAACAGAAUAGUUUUGGCAUUCAACAAACAUUGGCUGUUAUUAUAUUAGCUAUUAAAAAUUUAAGUCAUUUAGGUCAAUGAAACAGGAGGGUUUCCAGAAUUAUACCCAAUUAAUUAUACAUGGGAAGGUGAUGAAGGUAGCAUGUCAAAUUGGUAUAAAAAGAUGGAAUAUUAAAUAAGUGGGGAUACUGUAUCAGAUAGGAACAUAUUUGGUUGCAAGAAACAAAAAUUCCUGUGAUUACUAGCUUCACUGUGAGUUUAUUUUUUCACGUAAUAAAUCCAAGGUUACAUAAUCCAUAACUGAUAUGGCAGUUUAACAGUGUUAUUAAGAACUCAAGGUCCAUUUAUUGCUCUAUUCUGCCAUCUUUGGUGAGUGGCUUUCAUCCUCAUUGUCUCAGAAAAGUUAUUUCACCUCUAAGUAUUACAUCUACAUUUCAAGCAGGAAGAAGAUGAAGCUUAAGAGACCAAAUGGAGCAUGUCAGUCAAAGGUGUCCUUAUUUAAAAUCUCUGGAAGCCCCACUUAGUGGCUUCCAUCCAUGUCUCAUGGGACAGAACUGAAUCACAUAGCCAUCCCUUGCUGUAAGAGAGUUGGGGAAAGUAUUUUAAGCUGGGACAUCCCAGCCCUGAGUGAAGUCAGGGAUCUGUUAGGAAGAAUGGAUGCUAGGUAGGUAAAUGGCAAUGUCUGACAAAGACAUGGUAGGCCAGUCUGAAAAAUGUAAAGCUGGGCUGCGCGCGGUGGCUCACGCCUGAAAUCCCAGCACUUUGGGAGGCCGAGGCGGGCGGAUCCUGAGGUCAGGAGAUCGAGACCAUCCUGGUUAACGUGGUGAAACCCCGUCUCUACUAAACAUAUAAAAAAUUAGCCGGGCUUGGUGGCGGGCGCCUGUAGUCCCAGCUACUGAGGCAGGAGAGUGGCAUGAACCCGGGAGGCGGAGAUUGCAGUGAGCCGAGAUCGCGCCACUGCACUCCAGCCUGGGUGACAAGGCAAGACUCCGUCUCAAAAAAAAAAAGAAAAAUAUAAAGCUGGAUCUAUACCUCACUCCUUAUACCAAAGUACAUUACCCUUGUAUCAAAUAUUUUAAAAACUGGAAUAAGCUUUUCAUAUAAUCUUUGAGAAGAUGGGGCUUUCAAAGCGUUAAAUGAAACACAGAAGCCAUGGCCAGGCACGGUGGCUCAUGCCUGUAAUCCCAGCUCUCAGGGAGGCAAGAGGCAGGAGCAUAGCUUGAGCCCAGGCGUUCAAGACCUGCCUGGGCAAUAUAGCGAGACCCCGUUCUCCCCAAAAAGGAAAAAAAAAAAAAAACCAAAAAAAAAAAAAAAGUAUAAAGCACAGAAGCGAAAGGAAAAGUGAUGAAGACACUUGAAGACCUGUCAUUUAAAAUGAUUCUACAGGAAAAAGAUGAACUACAAAUUGGGGAAAAAUAUUUGUAGGACUUAUGUAGACAAAGGACUAAUUUUCUUAAUAAAAACAUUUAUCAGUAAAUUUAAAUGGGCAAAGGAAAUACUUGGACAAUCAUAUCAUGUAUGUAAUAUUAAUAUUUAUAAAUCAAUAAAAUGGGCUAGGGAUAUAAAUCAGCAAUUCAAGGGGAGGGUAAAAAGACCAACUAAUAUAUGUAAAGAUGCACAAAUUCAUUCAUGAUUAAAUGUGAAUUAACAACGUUGGCCUCUCGGAUUCCCAAAACUUUAAAAGAUUAAUAAUAUCCAGUAUUGGUUGGGAUUAUAAGCAGAUAUGAUAUUUCACUGAUAGAGACCAGCAUGACUGUCUCAAUUGUUAAACUAUUGAAAUGCAUCUGUGUCAAUGGUAAAUAGUAUUAUUGUAAGUACAACACUAAAAUUAAUAAAUUGUGUAAAUUCUAA